ACACACCGGGCCCGGCUCCUGAGGGCGCCAGCGCGGCCCCGGGGAGCGCGAGGAGCCGGCGAAGCGCGCGGCCUGCCGUUGGCGGCCUGGUCCGCAGCGCCCUGCGCCCACCCGCCCCGGACGUGGGGCCCAAGCCCCCGUGAAGAUGGUGUCCUGGAUGAUCUCCAGAGCCGUGGUGCUGGUGUUUGGAAUGCUUUAUCCUGCAUAUUAUUCAUACAAAGCUGUGAAAACAAAAAACGUGAAGGAAUAUGUUCGAUGGAUGAUGUACUGGAUUGUUUUUGCUCUCUAUACUGUGAUUGAAACAGUAGCCGAUCAAACAGUUGCUUGGUUUCCCCUGUACUAUGAGCUGAAGAUUGCUUUUGUCAUAUGGCUGCUUUCUCCCUAUACCAAAGGAGCAAGUUUAAUAUAUAGAAAAUUCCUUCAUCCACUUCUUUCUUCAAAGGAAAGGGAGAUUGAUGAUUAUAUUGUACAAGCAAAGGAACGAGGCUAUGAAACCAUGGUAAACUUUGGACGGCAAGGUUUAAACCUUGCAGCUACUGCUGCUGUUACUGCAGCAGUAAAGGAUUUCUGGCUUACUUCUGCACCUCUACUUCAAUCAAUUUGAGGUAACCGAUUAUUCAAAAUAAGGCAUGAAAAAGUCUGUUCUUAAAACUUGGUACUUAGCCAGUUACUAAUGUCAUUUGUUGUGUUUGCAAGCCAAGUUAUCAAAUGAAUGUGUUCUGUAAAAAUUUGCAUUAUGGUUUUGGAUUUCUUUGCAUGUUGUAAUUUGUGUGAUUUAUUUUAAAUACUUUAGCAUAAUUGAUUUUGGUGUGUUUGGUAUGGAAAGAAAAUAGCCUUCUGUGUUCCUUAGUUGCUUCAUGUAUAAAAUGGGGGUAAUAUACCUGUGAGAAUAUUUAAAAGCACAGUGCUUGCUUGCAUAUAGUAGGAGCCCAAUAAACAUAAAUAUCAUGUGUCUAUCUCCAUUCAAAAUUCAAGUGAAAAUUUAAGUUUUUUGCUAUUAAAUUAAAUUGAGAUUGAAUAGUAUUCUGCUUUCAAGUUAGUCUGUUUUAGUUAUCUUGAACUAAAACAACUCUAUGGAAAUAAAUAUUCCAGUUGAGUGGUGAUUUUAUAUAACUAAUAGUGAAGGGAUAUGAAAUGAGGGCACUUUCACUUUUCAGAGAGGUCUUUGACUCAAGUAUCAAAAUGAAUGUAAUGAACAAGAAGGAAAAUUCAAAUUAUAUACCUAAUAGCAUUACAUUGAGGGUUAAAUGGAAGUUUAUUAACUAUGCAGCACUAUACAUGUAAGAUAACUAUAUUAUUAAUGAUUAUUAAUGGUCAGCACUUUAAUAUAGCAUAGUUUUCUUGUUAUUUGGCUUUUAAAGGCUUUUUCUUUUAUUAGGAUAGGUUUAUAAAUGAAUACAGAAAUAGCAAAGUUUUCAGCUUAAAGGACUAUGUUUUAUUUUAGAAGUUCAUUUUGUUUUUUAUUUCUUGCUUAGUGAAAAUGCAUUCCUGAUUUCCAUAUCUGCUAAAAAAGAUUAUCCAGGAGAUAAUCCAGCCACUGGGAAUUCUAAAAAGAGGGAAUAGAUGCAAUUAUCAAAGAAAUAAUACAAUAAUAUUUCCCAGAACUGAAGGAUAUGAAUCUUCAGAUUGAAAGGACCCACCAAGUACUUAGCACAAUGAAUGAAAAGAAUGACUGACUCUAAGUGAAGUCAUUGGGUAUCCCAAAACACCAGUGAUAAGGAAAGAAUUCAUAAAGAUUCCAAAUAUAAAAAGCAUGUCACAUUUGGCCAGGCACAGUGGCUCACACAUGUAAUCCCAGCACUUUGGGAGGCCGAGGCAGAUGGAUCACUUAAGGUCAGGAAUUCAGACCAGCCUGGCCAACAUGGUGAAACCCCGUCUCUACUAAAAAUACAAAGAUUAGCUGGGCGUGGUGGGGGGGCGCCUGUAAUCCCAGCUACUCGGGAGGCUGAGGCAGGAGAAUUGCUUGAACCCGGGAGGCGGAGGCUGCACUGAGCCAAGAUCACACCACUAUACUCCAGCCUGGGUGACAGAGCGAGACUCCAUCUCAAAAAAAAAGCAUGUCACAUUUAAAUGAUGUAGAAUCAGAAUGACAUUAAAUUUCUAAACAGUGACAGUGAAAGCUUGAAGACAGUAAUACCAUCCAUGAUACCAUCAUGAUUUUCACCCUCAAGAACUAUUAACAGUCAAGCUCUCAAUUGUGUUAGCUUAGAAUUAAGAAAUUUCUUAAUUCUAGGCAUGCAGAGUCACAAGAUUUACCUACUGGUUAUCUUUUGUCCAGGCAGAUAUGCUCCCCAGAGCUAGGGAAUGGUCCACAAAAAAGAAAACCCAUGGGAUCUGGGAAACAAGUCAUUCAGCACAGAAAGGAGAUGACAAAAAUUCCCAAAGAGAACACCACACAGCAAGUCCAAAGUGCAGCCAGCCAAAACUGGAUGUGGUGGAUGAAAGGUGCCAGGAGGGAUGUCUCUGGUAGACCUACAAAGCCAAGAGGAUUUUUCGUGCUGCACAGGGAUGAUACUAAAACCAGUGAGAGGCUGGGCGUGGUGGCUCACACCUGUAAUCCCAGCACUUUGGGAGGCCGAGGUAGGUGGAUCACCUGAGGUCAGGAGUUCAAGACCAUCCUGGCCAACGUGGUGAAACCCAGUUUCUACUAAAAAUUCAAAAAAAUUAGCUGGACAUGGUGGUGGGCACCUGUAGUCCCAGCUACUCAGGAGGCCAAGACAGGAGAAUCGCUUGAACCUGGGAGAUGGAGGUUGCAGUGAGCCAAGAUCACGCCAUUGCACUCCAGCCUAGGUGACAAGAGUGAAACUCCAUCUCAAAAAAUACUAAUAAUAAAAUAAAUAAAUAAAUAAUAAAAAAUAAAAGCAGGGACUCUGAGGGCAUGCUUCAACCAGAUGACACAUUGGCUGUAGGCCACUGGUGCCCAUGUAGCUGCACAUGAUCCCUGAGCACCAUGAAAAAAUACAUUGGCGGCAAUGUAAAGAGGAAGAGGGUAAGACAAUGAAAAAGGAAAAAAAAAGGCAUAAUCAUUAACUCUGGGGAAAAAAGUUACAUAAGAAAUGAAAUAAUGGAGUAUGACUGCAUUUACAUUAUAAUAAUGAACACAGACUAAGGAUUUAACAACUGUGGUUUUGCCAUAUUGAGAGUAUGGGGGAAAGAGAAGGAAAGUGGAAGAGAACUAAAAUCCUCAUUUGUUACAGUAGGAAAGUAGAGGGUUUAAAGGAGUUGCAUCGGCAGCGGAUGAAGAGGAGAAGGAGACUAAGAGCUUGUUGCUUUUUGCUAUAAAAUUUAGCAUUUUUGAUUUUGCAAAUCAAGUGCAUGUAUUUAUUUACACCCAAUGAAGAUGCUAUCUGAAUUUUUCAUAUUUAAAAGCAUCCUUCAACAUGGUUCUAUGGAGAAAAACUGAAAAUUAAAUUUCAAGUUGAAAAAUUAUUUAGAGAACACAUUUUAGAAUAUUGUCUCAAAAAACAAAGAAGCAUACAAAUCCCAUUUUUCCUCCUCACUUUUAACAUUUGUGUAUAAUAAUCUAUUAUUCUCCUAUUUUGUGAGACACCAUUGUACAUAUUGUGACUAUUUUGUGCAGUACUUGUUUUAUUUUGACUUGUGUUUACUACUCCCACGUAGGGCAUCAGCAGUCCCCACUCUAUUAUCUUAUCCUCAUUCCCUUCCUCAUUUAUUUUUAUCUUACACUUCGCCUCCAUUGGUAUUUAGCAUUCUACAUAUUAUUUAUUCAGCAUCUGUUUAUUUAAUGCCUACUGCAUAGUAGGUACUGGGAAUGUAGCAAUGAACAAGAUAGAUAUAGCCCUCACCUGCACAAUCUACUGUCUGUCUGGAGCUAAUGUCUGUAUUAGCUAGGGAAUAGCCCACAAAAAUUUUAUUUCUAACUGAAAAUUUUAUUUCACCUCUGGUUGAUAAGACCCCACCCAUGGCUGGGCGCAGUGGCUCACACCUGUAAUCCCAGCACUUUGGGAGGCUGAGGCGGGCGGAUCACAAGGUCAGGAGAUUGAGACCAUCCUGGCUAACACAGUGAAACCCCAUCUCUACUAAAAAUACAAAAAAUUAGGUGGGCGUGGUGGUGGGUGCCUGUAGUCCCAGCAACUCGGGAGGCUGAGGCAGGAGAAUGGUGUGAACCCAGGAGGCGGAGCUUGCAGUGAGCCGAGAUCGCGCCACUGCACUCCAGCCUGGGUGAGAGUGCAAGACUCUGUCUCAAAAAAAAAAAAAAAAAAAAAAGACCCCACCCAUUACCCUUCAUUAUUAAAAUAAGCAUUAUCUCACAGGAAUACUUUUCUGUAAAAAUGCCACGAAAACAAAAAUGUGUCUAUUUCAUAUAUCUAUUUUUCUGGCUCUCUUGUGAUUUAUUCUUUUAAUUUAUACGUUUAACACCUUAAAAUCACGUGUUUUAAUUUAUACGUUAACACCUUAAAAUCACGUGUCCACCCCAAAGGCAGUAAUAUUGAUAAAAAUCAUCUAAGUCACUCCUGCAAAACAAGUAGAAGCCCAUAUCCCCUAAAUGAAAUCAGAUACUGGAUUUGGAACUGUUCCCAUUUGUUUGCAAUGUUGUGAUUCUUUUAUCCAUAACAUCCCUGUAUGUAAGGUAACCUUCAUUAUUCUCAUGAGUACCGGAAUGUUGGAGACCCCAUCCUGGAGUCUAUAUUAUUCACUAGCAUAUUCAUUAAAUAUGCUGAACAUAGCGUAAUGUUAACCCUAUUUGCCUCAAGUUAUACUGUGCUUAUUUUAAAGUACAUGAAAUUAGUUUCAUCUCUGCAGAUGUCAAACAAGGGCAUUGUCAUAGAAGAAUCACUGAACCAGACACUUCAUACUGAAGAGUAAAUUGAAACUGAAAUAGGAAAUAGGUCAGGUUUAAGGAGAAGCUGCAAGAAAGCCAACAGUAAGAUCUGAAAAUUAUUUAACAUUUUUACAAUAUAUAGUUUGUUUAAAGUAUCUUUCAGGCUUAAAAUUCUUGGACUCUUGGUGUGACCUUUGAAGAACGGGUAAUAACGCUGACUAGGUUUCCCAGGUUGAACCACCUGAGCAUGUUAAAGGUGAAAAUAGGAAUCUAAUCAGAACAUUUAUUACACCGUAAAGCAAUUUUCUGAAAAUGUUACUCAGUUCUAUGACCUCAUUACCAGGCAUCUGUUCGCAAGGUCACUGUACAAGUUUAUUUUGGCUGAGCAAAGCAUAAACAUUUGAAGGACCUUCAAGGAUUUUGCUGAGGAUGUACAGCAUUCCAUAGCUUUUCACAUGAGAAACAUAGGUGGUUUCGUGCAGAUGAGCAACACUACUGCCAGAUGAAGGACAGAUGAAGAAAAGUACUGUUAGUUGUAUUAACCAUGUCUUUGAAUUUCUCUGGCAGCCUUUUUUUGGUGAAUUUCUUUAGCAGAUAUAAGAAAUCAGUUACCACAGACUUUUGAGCUUUACAGGUAAAAUUGUUGAAAUCUAAUUAACUUUAAAUGAUCCCGAUUAGGUCAAAAAUCCGAACAUCUUACUGUCUAUGACUUUCUGUUUGUGAAUGGCUUUGAGGAUAUACAGCUUAGUAUUAUACACUUAAAAAAAAAGGGAAGAAUGUUUGUCCAGACAAUGGAAAAAGAAGGUUGUACUAUUUUUCCUAAAAUCUAGGGAAGCAGAAUGGUAUAACAAACAUUGAAUGCUACAGCAAUUGAGUUAAUCUGGAUUUUUUUUAGUGCUGAUUCCACCACAAAUUAGCCACGAGAUUUUGGGCAAAUCAUCUGCAUUGAUCUAAGCAUUAAUUUUUCUCACUUGUAAAACGAAGAGGUGAAACAUGAUUUCUAAAACCCCUUAUAUCUCUAAAACAGUGGUUCUCAACUAGAGGCAAUUUUGUGCCCCUACCCUUACCACGGGACAUUUUAGGUUGUCACCACUGAGAGGGGGCUGCUACUGGUAUCUAGUCGGUAAAGAAUGGUCAGGGAUGCUGCUUAAUAUUCUACAAAGCACAGGACGUUCCCCACAACAAAAAAUUAUCUAACAAAAAAUAGCAAGAGUGUUAAGGUUGAGAAACUGCUCUAAAAGUAUGAUGAGUCAGAAAAAACUAAAAGAAUAUAUAAAUAUGUAUAAGUAGUUUUGGUGGUAGGUUACAAAUAAUUUUUACUUCCUUUUUAAAAUUUUUCUCCAUGUUAUCAAUGUUCUUCAGUAAAUACGUAUUGCUUUAAACUCACUAAAAUAUUUUAUUCACCUAAUGCAAAUGCAGUCAAUUCCAUUCUGGGCUUGAUCAGAUUAAUUGUUAAAUGUGCAUGGGGAAAUGAGAUUUCCCUAAAAACUGGGAACUAACCUUAUCUGCAAUUAUAAUGUAACAUCAGGGAUCAACAAGAAAUAGAGCUUAGUGGCUAUUCUUUACUGAAUAGUAUAAUAAGAAUUAUUCUGUAAAAGAAUGUUUUGUGCUUGUACGAUUAUAAAGCAUUGCUGGUUAUAUGUUUUUAAAUCUGUGAUUUAAAAUGUGAAGAAAAUAAAGGUUUUAUACAAAGGUGCUGAUAAACAAAAUAAGUUCUUAUUUAAAACAAAAUAACUAAUGUUAAUGUAGUGUUUAACCAGGAAAUGAAGUAUUUAAACAAAGACAGCAUUAUUUGAGUGUAAAGAAAUUGGAAUUACUCAUACAUGCAGGGCCCCUUUUUAUGGAUGCCAACCACGUGCUUGGAUACUUGAGUAGACAUUCAGAUGUCCUAGUGCCCUUGGAUGUAAAUGAGCUCUGUGUGGAGCCAGUGUGGGGAGCUGCUUCUCAGCUGAAGAAUCCCUUCCAGAGCCUGAGUGUGCUAGCUCUGGACCCAGCCCUCCUGCCCAGUCAGCCCCUGCAGUAUUCUCAGUUUCUUACAGAGGCAUUUGGGCCCACCUAAAUCCAAAACCUGAGAAUUUAGUGCCAGCUGAAGUUCAGAUGGUUCAGAAACAGUUCUGCUCACGAUGAUCAGUUUCAAUGUGUAAAAUAUUCUACAGAAUACUUAAUUACCUGGACUUUUACAUUCUCAUCAUAAUCUCUGUUACUUUGAUUGUUAGGAUCAAUUUUAACAUACACAGAGUACAGACAAUUCUGCAGAGAAUAGGAUCUAAAGUGCUGAAAUAUGGAAUUAUCUUGUGAAUGGUAAUCCCGCCUUUCCUCUUUAUUGACUAAGACCGCUGUUUCCAUACAGCAGACUAGACUAGAACUUUUCUUUUUCUUUCUUUCUUUUUCUUUCUUUCCUUUCUUUCUUUCUCUCUCUCUGUCUCUCUCUUUCUCCCUCUCUUUGUUUCUUUCUCUCUCUCUCUUUCUUUCUUUGUCUUUCUUUCUUUCUGUCUUUCUUCUUUCCUUUUUUAGAGACAGGGUCUCGCUCUAUCACCCAGGCUGGAGUGCAGAGUUGUGAUCACAGCUCACUAAGGCCUCAAACUCCUGGCCUCAUGUGAUCCUCCCACCUUGGCCUCCCAAAGUGUUGGAAUUGCAGGCGUGAGCCACUGCACCAGGUCCUUUUCUCAUUUUUCUUAUACUUUUGUCUUAAUAUUAUAUAAAUUAAAUAGAAGAAAAUAGAUACACAAAGCAUUAUUAAUUUAAACAAAACCAAUCCCUUUUAGCAUUGUUAUUUACAAGUGACUAUAAUGUUCUAUUUGUGGCCUCAAAAAUAGACAUUUUUAUUUUAUUGAUGGGAAUAAAGCAUUAGAUACAGGACACAUGAGUGAGAAAUGGAUUGGAAAUUCUUAUAGUAUGCCACAUAUUGACUAAUUUUGUAAUAUUAAAGACAAUAUUUUAAAAAAGGAAAAAAGUCACCCAUCCCAUCUGCCUAAACAUUGUACUGUUGUUAGUUUUGCAUUUUUCCAUGCCUACUUAUAGCCAUACUGCAUACUUGCAAUCAUAUUAUGCAUGUGCUAUAGAAUUCUGGGGUAGAGGGAAGAUAUCUCCACUUACCGUUAAUAUAGCAAACAUAGUUCCUUUAUUACUGGACUUUUUGUGCUGAAGAUGUAAAAACUGGAAGGAAUAAGGUAGUCUUCAGAAGUGAUUACUUUGUAAUUAUACCCAUCCUUUAAACUGGUUACAUUGGAUACAUGUAAUUUACGUAAUGUUUUCAAAGUCCACAAUAUUGCACCAAUUUCUCUCUUAUAUUAGUUUUAUUCUGGAUCCAUAAAAAAUAUACAGUGGAAAGUCCAAUUUUCCAAGGUAAUAAUGGCUGUUAAAGUGUUGGAGGUUCUCAAAGAGGGCUCAUAUUCCCUUUUUGCUUUUCCCUACAGUGCCUGGCUUUCCUGAAAGCCUUGAAGAGGUUGAUAAUACUUGGGUAUUGAUAAUAGUAGCAUUGGUUACUCAAGAGCUAAAUUUAAAUCCAGCCUUUAGAUAGAUCACCCAGAUACCUCAAGGUUGGGCCUUGCCUUGCUCAUGUUUAUUCUGAACCUGAAGCAAACCCUUGGUAGGUGGUGUAGUCUAUCCAUGGAGAAACCUGUGGCCAUACCUGUAGUUUGCUGCUGAACCUCUGCAAAAAACCUACAGUGUUUACAUUAAAACAUGCUGCCAUCUAUGGAGAAGUCUUUAACAGUCAAGAGUAAUGAAAAAGAAGGGACAUAAAAAGAGUAUUUAGUUUACUUAUUACAUGCUCAAUAUCAGUAGCAUACCAGGCACACCAGGAGAAUAGAAGAAGCCUAAGAUUUGUCCCUCUCCUCUAGUGUCUUAAAAGUCUUGCUCUGGAGGCAAAAUAUACCUAUCCCAACAAUAGAAGUAACAGUAGUACGUGAGUUCAUUUGUGAGGUAUAUCCCAAGAGAUUUGUUGAUUAUGCUUGUUAAACAUACCAAAGUUUGGGGAUGAUAUAAUUAUAAAGCUAGACUGAUUCCAUUGUACUUUGAGUCAUUUGUAUCCUGAAAUGUACCUUCUUGAGUGGGAGGGUUUGGGAAUUAUAGCCAGCCUUGGAAAUCGCAUGUGAAUUGAGUAAAGGGUAUCAUGGACAUGCAUGUCAUUUGUCAUCUGUGUGGCAGUAAAUAAAGAAAUCAGAAAUUGCUGAGAGAAGGCACAGAACUACGAAGAUGAAAUAAAGAGAAUGACAUUUCUGAGAAACAAGGCAUCCGUUUCAGAUGAACACUGGUCACUUCCUCGUAGUAUGUCUCUGGAGUCUUCUGUCAACUAUCUGUUUGAUAAGUAAAUGAUAUCUAAUAAGGAGGAAGCAAGUAUAAUAAAUUAAUCCAUGCCACAAA